GGCUCUCUACCUCUCGCCGCCCCUAGGGAGGACACCAUGGGCCCACUGAUGGUUCUUUUUUGCCUGCUGUUCCUGUACCCAGGUCUGGCAGACUCGGCUCCCUCCUGCCCUCAGAACGUGAAUAUCUCGGGUGGCACCUUCACCCUCAGCCAUGGCUGGGCUCCUGGGAGCCUUCUCACCUACUCCUGCCCCCAGGGCCUGUACCCAUCCCCAGCAUCACGGCUGUGCAAGAGCAGCGGACAGUGGCAGACCCCAGGAGCCACCCGGUCUCUGUCUAAGGCGGUCUGCAAACGUGAGGCUCCCUGUGGGCUUUGCUCAGGCUGUGCGCUGUCCAGCCCCUGUCUCCUUUGAGAAUGGCAUUUAUACCCCACGGCUGGGGUCCUAUCCCGUGGGUGGCAAUGUGAGCUUCGAGUGUGAGGAUGGCUUCAUAUUGCGGGGCUCGCCUGUGCGUCAGUGUCGCCCCAACGGCAUGUGGGAUGGAGAAACAGCUGUGUGUGAUAAUGGGGCUGGCCACUGCCCCAACCCAGGCAUUUCACUGGGCGCAGUGCGGACAGGCUUCCGCUUUGGUCAUGGGGACAAGGUCCGCUAUCGCUGCUCCUCGAAUCUUGUGCUCACGGGGUCUUCGGAGCGGGAGUGCCAGGGCAACGGGGUCUGGAGUGGAACGGAGCCCAUCUGCCGCCAACCCUACUCUUAUGACUUCCCUGAGGACGUGGCCCCUGCCCUGGGCACUUCCUUCUCCCACAUGCUUGGGGCCACCAAUCCCACCCAGAAGACAAAGGAAAGCCUGGGCCGUAAAAUCCAAAUCCAGCGCUCUGGUCAUCUGAACCUCUACCUGCUCCUGGACUGUUCGCAGAGUGUGUCGGAAAAUGACUUUCUCAUCUUCAAGGAGAGCGCCUCCCUCAUGGUGGACAGGAUCUUCAGCUUUGAGAUCAAUGUGAGCGUUGCCAUUAUCACCUUUGCCUCAGAGCCCAAAGUCCUCAUGUCUGUCCUGAACGACAACUCCCGGGAUAUGACUGAGGUGAUCAGCAGCCUGGAAAAUGCCAACUAUAAAGAUCAUGAAAAUGGAACUGGGACUAACACCUAUGCGGCCUUAAACAGUGUCUAUCUCAUGAUGAACAACCAAAUGCGACUCCUCGGCAUGGAAACGAUGGCCUGGCAGGAAAUCCGACAUGCCAUCAUCCUUCUGACAGAUGGAAAGUCCAAUAUGGGUGGCUCUCCCAAGACAGCUGUUGACCAUAUCAGAGAGAUCCUGAACAUCAACCAGAAGAGGAAUGACUAUCUGGACAUCUAUGCCAUCGGGGUGGGCAAGCUGGAUGUGGACUGGAGAGAACUGAAUGAGCUAGGGUCCAAGAAGGAUGGUGAGAGGCAUGCCUUCAUUCUGCAGGACACAAAGGCUCUGCACCAGGUCUUUGAACAUAUGCUGGAUGUCUCCAAGCUCACAGACACCAUCUGCGGGGUGGGGAACAUGUCAGCAAACGCCUCUGACCAGGAGAGGACACCCUGGCAUGUCACUAUUAAGCCCAAGAGCCAAGAGACCUGCCGGGGGGCCCUCAUCUCCGACCAAUGGGUCCUGACAGCAGCUCAUUGCUUCCGCGAUGGCAACGACCACUCCCUGUGGAGGGUCAAUGUGGGAGACCCCAAAUCCCAGUGGGGCAAAGAAUUCCUUAUUGAGAAGGCGGUGAUCUCCCCAGGGUUUGAUGUCUUUGCCAAAAAGAACCAGGGAAUCCUGGAGUUCUAUGGUGAUGACAUAGCUCUGCUGAAGCUGGCCCAGAAAGUAAAGAUGUCCACCCAUGCCAGGCCCAUCUGCCUUCCCUGCACGAUGGAGGCCAAUCUGGCUCUGCGGAGACCUCAAGGCAGCACCUGUAGGGACCAUGAGAAUGAACUGCUGAACAAACAGAGUGUUCCUGCUCAUUUUGUCGCCUUGAAUGGGAGCAAACUGAACAUUAACCUUAAGAUGGGAGUGGAGUGGACAAGCUGUGCCGAGGUUGUCUCCCAAGAAAAAACCAUGUUCCCCAACUUGACAGAUGUCAGGGAGGUGGUGACAGACCAGUUCCUAUGCAGUGGGACCCAGGAGGAUGAGAGUCCCUGCAAGGGAGAAUCUGGGGGAGCAGUUUUCCUUGAGCGGAGAUUCAGGUUUUUUCAGGUGGGUCUGGUGAGCUGGGGUCUUUACAACCCCUGCCUUGGCUCUGCUGACAAAAACUCCCGCAAAAGGGCCCCUCGUAGCAAGGUCCCGCCGCCACGAGACUUUCACAUCAAUCUCUUCCGCAUGCAGCCCUGGCUGAGGCAGCACCUGGGGGAUGUCCUGAAUUUUUUACCCCUCUAGCCAUGGCCACUGAGCCCUCUGCUGCCCUGCCAGAAUCUGCCGCCCCUCCAUCUUCUACCUCUGAAUGGCCACCCUUAGACCCUGUGAUCCAUCCUCUCUCCUAGCUGAGUAAAUCCGGGUCUCUAGGAUGCCAGAGGCAGCGCACACAAGCUGGGAAAUCCUCAGGGCUCCUACCAGCAGGACUGCCUCGCUGCCCCACCUCCCGCUCCUUGGCCUGUCCCCAGAUUCCUUCCCUGGUUGACUUGACUCAUGCUUGUUUCACUUUCACAUGGAAUUUCCCAGUUAUGAAAUUAAUAAAAAUCAAUGGUUUCCACA